GAAGACGUGGGGACGCAGGCGGGUCGUAGAGAGCGUGAGUUUCCGCGUCUGUUUGGUCCGGCUGCUGUCGUUGGUUGUGAGCGGCAUCUCUCGCCGUUUCCCCGGGCUGCGGGAGCUGGCGGCCGGGCUGGGGCUGCUGGGCGGAGGUCGGCGCCUCCCGGGGGGCUAGGGCGAGGGAGGCAUGGCGGGGCUGGAGGCACAGCCUCCCCGUCCGGGGCAAGUCCGAGAGCGGGGAGGGCGUUUCCUGGGGUAACUCCACCUGGGGUCUUGUCGAAGUUGCCGCAUCUCCGCCGGACCGCACGGGAACGACGUGCCCACACUCGGAGGAAGGGGUUGGCGCUGAGCGAGUUUAAAGGGUUCCUUUUGAAAGCAGGAAGUUUGAAGUGACGUUGCAUCAGCAACAGAGCAUGCAGUUUCAGGUGCUCUCGGGACAGCUUUCAGUUUCUCAGAACAAGUCUAAGCCUCACCGCAGUAAUAACUUUUAUUAGAGGACAAAAAAUCCGCCAAAGUAAACCCUUUCUGUCCAACCCCUAAAAACCUUUGGAUAAACGUUUACAAGAAACGGAUCACAGCCUUAUUUGUUUUUCUAAACUGAGCAUAAACUCUUUUGAAGACUCAGCGUUACUGUCAAAAUGAAUGAGUGCCUGCCUAGUUAUGAUUCAAUUAUCGAGGUGUUUGGGUCUCUGCAGUACACUCAGUGACUCCCAGGCUUUUCUUUUUUCUCUUUGAAAUUGCUUAUUAGAAGGCUUUAUCUAAUUUCUCACAGUUGUGUGUCUUUUUGAGGUAGUUCUAAUAAACUUUAAAGGCUUCUGGUUUGCUGCAGGCCUGCCGUCGCUGUGGAAAGCAAGUAUUCUUUCAAAGAAGAAUAGAAGUGCAUUGGUUUCUAAAUAAUCCCAGGACGCUAGGAUCAGCAUCACUUGGGAACUUCUUGGAAAUGCACAUUUUGGGGUCUUAUCCCAAACUUACUGAAUCAGAAAUAUAUUUUAACAAGCCUUCCAGUUGAUACCAAUGCACCUGGACGCUAAAGUUUGAGAAUUAAUGGCGUAGUGAUAACACCCAUUGUGGAAUCACAUAUAAUGGAAUUUGAAUUGAAGUAAUUCCUAGAUGGAAAAACUUGGACAUGUUACCUCACAGGGCUGGAAUAUGAAGAUGCAAGAAAAAUGUUUAACACAAAACACAUAGAAAACCCUCAAAGAUGUUAUUAAGUAACUUAUUAGAACUGCAUAAAAUAAGUACAUAGUUUGUGCUGGAAGGAUUCUUCAGCGGGGUAGAUAUGAGCUGUAGCGCAUGGAUAUUGGGACUGCUGCUUAGAGGGUAUUUUGUUUACCUCGGGAUUCUCAAUUCUGUGUAGUCAAGGUUGUUGGAUGCAGGAUAUUCAGUUAAAAGUUAAAGCAGUGCAUACUAAUGCUAUUGUGGUUGUAGGAUUUUUAAGAAUAGCAUUAGUAUUUAUGUUGAAGAGUAGUUUUUAAUUCUUUGGCCUUCUGAUCUCUUCAGCUUUGUUUGGAGACAGUCUCUUUCUGCCACCCAGGCUGGAGUGCAAUGGUGCAAUCUUGGAUCACUGUAACCGCUGCCUCCAGGGUUCAAACGAUUCUCCUGCCUCAGCUUCCCAGGUAGCUGGGAUUACAGGCGUCUGCCACCACGCCCAGCUAAUUUUUGUAUUUUUAGUAGAGACGGUUUCACCACGUUUGCCAAGCUGGUCCCGAACUCCUGACCUCAGGGGUCCAUUGUAGGGGGAGAAAGAAAUAUUCAGGAUUUAAAGCAGCUGCUCUAAAGGCUACAUUCACUGCAAUGUUGAGAAGGGAGCCUCUUAAACAGAAUCUUACCUGUAAAACUCAGGAGCCGAGAAGCUUUAAGAACAGUGAGGUUGAAGGGCACAGGCUCUUGGUCCUUGGCAGCGAUAUUAGGAGGCGUGCCUAGGGAACCUCGGAUUCCGGGGAGCUGGACGUGAAACUCUGUGGUGGAAUAGAAAUCCUCAGGGCAUGAGCUAUACCUAAAACGUAAUGGUAUUAAGAAUUCUGGUUCAGCCGUCUGUAUAUCUCCCCAGAUACCUGAAACUGACCACCUGAGUACGUUUUCCCAUUGCUGAGCUGUUUCCCUGAUAUCUGGCCAUGCAACGGAGAUCAAGAGGGAUAAAUACUGGACUUAUUCUACUCCUUUCUCAAAUCUUCCAUGUUGGGAUCAACAAUAUUCCACCUGUCACCCUAGCAACUUUGGCCCUCAACAUCUGGUUCUUCUUGAACCCUCAGAAGCCACUGUAUAGCUCCUGCCUUAGUGUGGAGAAGUGUUACCAGCAAAAAGACUGGCAGCGUUUACUGCUCUCUCCCCUUCACCAUGCUGAUGAUUGGCAUUUGUAUUUCAAUAUGGCAUCCAUGCUCUGGAAAGGAAUAAAUCUAGAAAGAAGACUGGGAAGUAGAUGGUUUGCCUAUGUUAUCACCGCAUUUUCUGUACUUACUGGAGUGGUAUACCUGCUCUUGCAAUUUGCUGUUGCCGAAUUUAUGGAUGAACCUGACUUCAAAAGGAGCUGUGCUGUAGGUUUCUCAGGAGUUUUGUUUGCUUUGAAAGUUCUUAACAACCAUUAUUGCCCUGGAGGCUUUGUCAACAUUUUGGGCUUUCCUGUACCGAACAGAUUUGCUUGUUGGGUCGAACUUGUGGCUAUUCAUUUAUUCUCACCAGGGACUUCCUUCGCUGGGCAUCUGGCUGGGAUUCUUGUUGGACUAAUGUACACUCAAGGGCCUCUGAAGAAAAUCAUGGAAGCAUGUGCAGGCGGUUUUUCCUCCAGUGUUGGUUACCCAGGACGGCAAUACUACUUUAAUAGUUCAGGCAGCUCUGGAUAUCAGGAUUAUUAUCCGCAUGGCAGGCCAGAUCACUAUGAAGAAGCACCCAGGAACUAUGACACGUACACAGCAGGACUGAGUGAAGAAGAACAGCUCGAGAGAGCAUUACAAGCCAGCCUCUGGGACCGAGAAGGAGUCUCUCCCCAAAGCCACCAUAUUGGGAAUGUGCUUGGGUCAAACCUGAAGCCAGCAUGUCUCUGAGUCUCACCCAGAUACCAUGGGGUAAGUACUGCCUGUUUACCACAGUGGCCUAUUCAGGUCCCUAGAGCCCUUUAGUCAGCAGGUGAUGAAUCCUGCUAGGAUUGAGUCUUUCUCUUCAAGGCAGAAGGUUUUCUUCUGGCCAGGGUGCGUCUAGAAAUGAUGUCUGGUAACUAGAGCCUGGAAUAGGGGCCUCAGGACUCUGCUCGGUACCCUAUCCUACUGUGGCUGAGCUGGUAUCCAAGUCGCAAAACAAAUUUGUCUUUACUCUUCCGUUUUCUCUCCUCAAGCACUGGGAAAUAGUCUCUUCCAGAGCUGCGAGUUGCAGUGCCUGAGGUUGGGAGAGGGGUAACACAAGCACUGACUUGGCUGUCCCGGCUGAUGUCUCACUGGAAGGCAUGUCCCCCAGGUCCACUGGCUCUGAGCCCAGCACAGCACCAGAGCUUACCCAAGAAUUGCAGUUCUUGUGACUCAGACUACCUUUCAAGUUUAUUUAGGACCCCAGAGCACUUUUGCCCAUGGUGUCAGGGCCUGAUGGAACUCAGGUUCUGACCACUGGGAUGGGCAAUUCCCCUCUGGCCUAGGCGGGUCUAAAUGCUCACUCCCUGGGUGCUGGCUAAGUUCUGCCCAGUUUUGCUUUCUGGCAGUGCUGAGUUCCAAUGGGAUGUCCACAAUCACUGUGCUCUCCCUCCCCCAAGUACACAGAUUCUCUGUCUAUGCUACCAGGGGAUGGAUGAGGAGUGGCAUUGGCAAUUCAAGACUAUCUUUCCUUCUCCCUUCAGUGCCUCUUUCAGUGUUGUGAAGUUAAAACCAGGUACUGUGAUCACUCACAUGAUCUUUGGUUCUUAUGAAGGUGAUUUUUUCUGCAGAUAGUUCUUCAGUUUGGUGUUCCUCUGGGAAGGAUGAUCUGUAAAGCUUUCUAUUUGGCCGUUUUGCUCCACCUCCCUCCAUCUCACCACAUUUAAUGUUGGUAGUGAUAACAGACAUUUCUAUAUGCUGCUGAUAUGAAUGCAAAUUGGUAUAACCUUUCUGGAAAACACAUUGGAAAUGUAUAAUCAAGAGGCUUACCUUCAGUGAUUCCUUGACUAGGAAUCUAGCCUGAGGAAAUAAUAGAGAGAUGGUCCAAUAUUUGUUUUUAAGUUACUGAUUCCCUAAUUAAAUUUAGUAACAAAAACUUAAAUACAUUGAAAUUUGCACAACAAUGUGUGCAAGGGUUAAAUCAGUUGUGGUUUCAUUGUAAAAUGGAAAUAUUAGGCAUCUAUUAAAAAUAACAUUUUUGAAAAAUUUAGUGGCAUGAAAAUAUGAUUACAACAUAAUUGCUGAAUGAAAAAACGUAAGGCACAAAAUAGUAUGUACCAUAUGGCCAGAAAUUUAUAAAAUAAGCCAACUCAAACCAAAUAUUUUUCCUUAGGAAAAAAAAAUGAAAACGGCCUUUGACAAAUGUCUUCUUGAUUCUUACACUUAGACAAUUACAAUGGUUUCAAAGGAAAAUAAAAUUCAAAUUAAUAUAAAUUUUUAUAAAGCUGCUUCCUUUGCCAUUGUUAGUUACUGUAUAAGGCACUUCAAGAGUCUUUUUAGACCUGUUUCCUUGAAACUAGUUUCGUGUGCUGUUCAAAACAUUCAUUCAAAAUAAAAUUCUGUGGUCAAAUAAGCUUGGGAAAUAUGUAAUUAAUUGGUUUCUUAAUUGCAGAGCUAAUUAGAAUCAUAAGUAGCAUACCAGUGUCAUUGUGGAUAUUCAAGGAGGUAUGGUUUGCAGUAUUUCCCAAAUUUAUUUGAAUGUAGAGUUUGUGUGUUUGUGUGUGUGUGUUUCAGAGGGGAAAGGGAAGAGGAGGAGAGGGAGGGAGGAUAGAAGAGAGAAACUAGAAUUGUUUGGGCUGAACCCUCUGACAGGUUGGAGACAUCCUGUUACUUUGCCUCUAAAUCCUUCAAUGUGUAUCUUUUGAAAAAUAAGGGCCAUUGGCCAGGUGCAAUGGCUCACGCCUGUAAUCCCAGCACUUUGGGAGGCCGAGGCGGGUGGAUCAUGAUGUCAGGAGAUCGAGACCAUCCUGGCUAACACAGUGAAACCCCGUGUCUACUAAGUAAAUAAAAAAAAAAAAAAAAUAAGGGCCAUUGUGCUACUUAUCUACAACAUCAUGGCCACAUCAAAGAAAAUUAGCAGGAAUUCCCUAGUAACACCUACCAUUUAGUCCAAAUAUGAAAUUUUCUAAUUUUCUCAAAGAGUAUGUUUUAUAGUCAGGUUUUCAAGGUUCUGAUGUUGCAUUUGAUUAUUUCUUUUUAAUAUAAAAACCAUACCGUGCCCUUUUUAUGAUUUAAUUUUUCAGGACACCAGUCUCAUUGAAUGGUAGGUGUCUUAUUAUUUCUUUGUGGUGUAUUUAAAUAGUUAGUUCUGUGUAUUUCUGUAUAUAUUGGCACUUACAUUUGAGGACUUGAUUAAUUGGAUUUGGGUUACACAUUUUUAGCAAGAAAAUGUCAUAGGUAACACUGUGUUCUUCAGAUUGCAUCAGGUCAGGAGAUACACUGUGUCAAGCCAUACCACUAAUACCUGGUUACUAGUUUCAGAAAGUGACUGACAAGUCUCUCUGUUGCAAAGGUACAUUUUUCCCUUUGCUGUUUGCAAGUUCCACAUGAAGUGAUACUAUGUCACCAUAUGAAUAUCCUGUUUCCUAAAAAUUACUUGAAAACCUUUCAAGUAAUGGUUUUUGUAGUCUUUGGUGAUCUUUUUUUACAAGGCUAAAUAUUAGUCUUGUAUUAUGCACUUCUGUAUAAAAACUGAUCACCUAUCAGUUAUUUCUUUGGGUUCCUUGUUAAUAUUUUUAUUUCUUUAAAAUUUAUAGUGAAAUUUACUCCGUGUGGUGUACACUUAUGUGAGCUUUGACAGAAGUAUAGAGUGGUUUAUCAUAACAAUCUAGAUACAGCACAGUUGUAUCACUCCAGAAAAUUACCCAUCACUCUCCCUUUGUAGUCAACCUACUCUGACCCUUAAUCCUCAACAAGCACUGUUCUCUUCUCCAUCUCCUUAACUUUGCUUUUUCCAGCAUGUCAUAUAAAUGAAAUCACACAGUAUUUAGCUUUGAGAGGUCGUACUUCUUUCCCUGAGCAAAGUUUAUUUGUUAUUCAUCUCUUUCUAUUAACUAUAUUGAUAAUUUUUUUUCUUUUAUGGUUGAAUUAUACUCUAGUGUAUAGAUAUACCAGAAGUUUUUUUUUGUUUUUUUGUUUUUUUGUUUUAAUCCUUUCACCAGUUGAAGGAUAUUUGGGUUGAUUCCAGGUUUGACAUUUAUGAAUAAAGCUGCUAUAAAAAUUUACGUACCGGAAUUUGUGUAAAUAUAAGUUUUCAUGUCACCUAGGUAAGCACAUAGGAGUAGGGUUUCUGGAUUAUAUAUGGUAAAUUUAUGUUUAACUUUAUAAGAAUCUGCCUGUUUUCCUAAGUGUUUGUACCAGUUUUCGUUCCUGCCGGCAGUAUAUGAGAGUUCCAGUUGCUCUCGGUUCUCCCAGCAUUUGGUAUUUUCAGUUGUUUUUAUCUUAGCCAUUCAAAUAGGCGUGAGGUUGCAGUUUUCAUUUAUAUUUCUCUAAUGACUAAUGAUGUUUCUGUUUAUCGACUACCUAUAUAUCUUCUUUGCUGAAGUUUCUGUUCCAUUAUUUUGUCUACUUUUAAUUGGAUUGUUUGUUUUCUUAUCUUUGAGUUUAGGGAAUUCUUUAUAUAUUCUGAAUAAAAGCGCUUCAUAAGAUAGGUGAUUUGCAAAUAUUUUCCCUGAGUCUGUGGCUUUUUCCCCCAUUCUCUUAAAAGUAUCUUUUGUGGCACAAAAGUUUAUAAUUUUGAUGAAGCACAAUUUAUCAAUGUGUCAAGCAUUUAGUGUUGUAUCUAAGAAUCUUUUGAUGUAACCCAAGACCAUGAUUUUCUGCUACAUUUUCUUUUAGGAGUUCCAUGGUCUUAAAAUUUACAUUUAGAUAUAUAGCCCAUUUUGAGUUAGUUUUUAUAUAAGAUGUGAGGUAUGAACCAAAGUUUGUUUUUUGCUUGUGGACUUCCAAAUAUUUCAGCACCAUUUGUAAAAAUGACUAUCAGUUCUCCAAUGAAUUGCCUUUGUACUUUUUUCAAAUAACAAUUGAAUAUGUUUACAUCAGUCUAUUUCUGAAAAUGUAAAAAACUUGAAGUCAUAUCAGAUAUCUUCUCAGACCAUUGCAGAGUAAAACUAGAAAUCAGUUCUAAAAGGAAUCCACAAAACCAUAUAAAUACAUGGAAAUUAAGCAAAUCUGCUCCUUUAUGAUUUUUGGGUUAACAAUGAUAUCAAGAUGGAAAUUAAAUAAUUCUUCAAGAUAAAUGAUAAUAGUGACACAAGAUAUCAAAACCUCUGGGAUACAGCAAAAGCAGUGCUAAGAGGAAACUUUAUAGGGCUAAAUGCCUACAUCAGAAAGUCUGAAAGAUCACAAAUUGACAAUCUAAUGUCACACGUCAAGGAAGUAGAGAAAUGAGAACCAACUAAACCUAAAGCUAGAAGAAGAAAAAAAAUAACAAAGAUCAGAGCAGAAUUAACAGAAAUUGCAACAACAACAACAACAAAAAAGAUCAUGAAACAGAAAGUUGGCUCUUUGAAAAGAUAAACAAAAUCAUAGACCGUUAGCUAUCUUAACCAUGAAAAGAAGAGAGAAGAUUCAAAUAAGCUGAAUUAGAAAUGAAAAUGGAGACACUACAACCAUCACCACAGAAAUACAAAAGACCAUUUGAGAUUACUGUGAACACCUCUAUGCAUACAAACUAGAAAAUCUAGAGGAAAUGGAUAAAUCCCUGGAAAUAUACAACCCUCCUAGCUUUAAUCAGCAAGAAAUAGAAAUCCUGAACAGACCAAUAACAACCAGUGAGAUUGAAUCCAUAAUUUUUUAAAUUGCCAACAAAAAAAACCCAGUGCCAGACAGAUUCACAGCCAAAUUCUACCAGACAUUCAAAGAAUUGGUACCAGUCCUACUGAAACUAUUCCAAAAGACUGAGAAAGAGGGAAUCGUCCCUAAUUCAUUCUAUGAAGCCGGUAUCACCAUGACACCAAAGCCACAAAAGGACAUAACAAAAGAAUAAAAAUACAGACAAAUAUCUCUGAUGAACGUAGAUGCAAAAACUCUCAACAAAAUGCUAGCAAACUGAAUCCAACAGCACAUCCAAACAAUAAUUUACCAUGAACAAAUGAGUGUCAUCCCAGGGUAGCAGGAAUGGUUCAACAUUCACAAGUCAAUAAAUGUGAUUCAUCACACAAACAGAAUUAAAAACAAAAACCAUAUGAUCAUCUCAAUUGAUGCAUAAAAAGCAUUUGCUAAAGUCCAGCAUCCAUUUAUGAUAAAAAAUGUCAACAAACUAGGAAUCGAAGGAAUAUACCUCAACAAAAUAAAAGCUAUCUGUGACAGACUUACAGCCAAUAUCAUACUGAAUGGGAGAAAAGGUGAAAAGAAUUCCCUCUAAGAACUGGAACAAGAUAAGGAUGCCCGCUUUCACCACUCUAUUCAACACAUUACUGGAAGUCCUAGCUAGAGCAGUCAGGCAAGAAAAAGAAAGGACGUUCAAAUUAGAGAGAGUCAAAAUGUCUCUGUUUGCUGAUGAUAUGAUUGUAUGCUUGGAAAACCCAAAAGACGACUCCAAAAGACUUCCUAGAUUUUAUAAAUGAAUUCAGUAAAGUCUUAGGUUAUAAAACUAAUGUAUACAAAUCAGUAGCACUGCUACACACCAACAGCCACUAAGCUGAGAAUCAAAUCCAAAACUCAACCCCUUUUAUGAUAGCUGCAAACAAACAAAACAAAAAACAAAACAAAACAAAACAAACUGGGGAUAAACUUAACAAAGGAGGUCUCUACAAGGAAAACUAUAAAAUACUACUCAAAUAAAUCAUAGAUGAUACAAACAAACAAAUGUAUGUCCCAUGUUCAGGUAUUGGAAGAAUCAAUAUCAUGAAAAUGACCAUAAUGCCUAAAGCAAUCUGCAUAUUCAAUGCAAUUCCUAUCAAGAUACUAACACUGUUUUUCACAGAAAUGUAAAAAAUAACCCAAAAAUUCAUAUGGAACCAAAAAAGAGCCUGAAUGCCAAAGCAGUCCGAAGCAAAAAGAACAAUCCAGAGGCAUCACAUUACCUGACUUCAAAUUACACUACAAGGAUGUAGUAACUAAAACAGCAUGGUACUGCUGUAAAAGUCGAUACAAAGACCAAUGGAACAGAAUAGAGAACCCAGAAAUAAAGCCAAAUACUUAAAACCAGCUGAUCUUCAACAAAACUUAAACAUUAAUUGAGGAAUGGACACCCUAUUCAAUAAAUGGUGCUGGGAAAACAGCCACAUGCAGAAUAUGAAACUAUCCCUAUCUCUCACCAUAUAAAAAAUUAAAAUCAAUUAGAGACUUAAAUCUUAAGACCUGAAACCAUAAGAAUUCUAGAAGAAAACCUAGGAAAAACUUCCCUGGACAUUGGCCUAGGCAAAGAAUUUAUGACUAAGACCCCAAAAGCAAAUGCAACAAAAACAAAAAUAAAUAAAUGGGAGCCAGUUAAAUUAAGUUUCUGCAUGGCAAAAGAAAUAAUUAUCAGAGUAAAAUACAACCCACAGAAUGGGAGGAAAUAUUUGCAAAUUAUGUAUCUGACAAAGGACUAAUAUCCAGAAUCUACAAUGAAUUCGAACAAAUCAACAAGAAAAAAAAAUAAACCUGUCAAAAACUGGGCAAAUGACAUGAAUAGACAUUCCUCAAAAUAAUACAUACAAAUGACCAAGAAACGUAUGAAAAAAAUGCUUAACAUCACUAAUCAUCAGGGAAAUGCAAAUUCAAACCACAAUAUGAGAUACUACCUUACCCCAACUGGAGUGGCCAUUACUAAAAAGUCAAAAAGCAAUAGAUGUUAGUGUGAAUGUGGGGAAAAGGGAAUGCUUAUACACUGAUGGUAGGAAUGUAAAUUAGUUACCUCUAUGGAAAACAGUACAGAGAUUCUUCAAAGAACUAAAUGUAGAUCUUCCAUUUGAUUCAGCAUUCCCACCACUGAUUAUCUACUCAAAGGAAAAGUCAUUAUAUCAAAAGAAGUCAUUAUGCACACCUGCAUGCAUAUGUUUAUUGCAGCAUAGUUAACAGUUGCAAAGAUACGGAAACAAGUGUCCAUCAACCAAUGAGUAAAGAAAAUGUGAUAUAUAUACACCAUGGAAUGCUACUCAGCCAUAAAAAAGAAUGAAAUAAUGUCUUUUGCAGCAACUUAGAUGGGGCUGCUGGAGGCCAAUAUUCUAAGUAUUAAUAACUCAGGAAUAGAAAACCAAAUACCAUAUGUUCUCACUUAUAAGUGGGAGCUAAACUAUGAGUAUGCAAAGACAUACAGAGUGGUUUAACAGACUUUUGAGACUCAGAAGGGGAAAGGGUGAGAAAGGGGUGAGAGAUUAAAAAGCCUACAUAUUGGAUACAAUGUACACUACUUGGGUGAUGAGUGCACUAAAAUCUCAGACUUCACCACUAUACAAUUCAUCCAUGUAACUAAAAAUUACUUGUACCCCUAAAGCUACUGAAAUAAAAAAAAUUGAAAAUCUA